ACACGCGCCUCUUCACGAGGUGGAAACAAGAUGGAGGAUUCGGCCUCGGCCUCGCUGUCUUCUGCAGCCGCUACUGGAACCUCCACCUCGACUCCAGCGGCCCCGACAGCACGGAAGCAGCUGGAUAAAGAACAGGUUAGAAAGGCAGUGGACGCUCUCUUGACGCAUUGCAAGUCCAGGAAAAACAAUUAUGGGUUGCUUUUGAAUGAGAAUGAAAGUUUAUUUUUAAUGGUGGUAUUAUGGAAAAUUCCAAGUAAAGAACUGAGGGUCAGAUUGACCUUGCCUCAUAGUAUUCGAUCAGAUUCAGAAGAUAUCUGUUUAUUUACGAAGGAUGAACCCAAUUCAACUCCUGAAAAGACAGAACAGUUUUAUAGAAAGCUUUUAAACAAGCAUGGAAUUAAAACCGUUUCUCAGAUUAUCUCCCUCCAAACUCUAAAGAAGGAAUAUAAAUCCUAUGAAGCCAAGCUCCGCCUUCUGAGCAGUUUUGAUUUCUUCCUUACUGAUGCCAGAAUUAGGCGGCUCUUACCCUCACUCAUUGGGAGACAUUUCUAUCAAAGAAAGAAAGUUCCAGUAUCUGUAAACCUUCUGUCCAAGAAUUUAUCAAGAGAGAUCAAUGACUGUAUAGGUGGAACAGUCUUAAACAUUUCUAAAAGUGGUUCUUGCAGUGCUAUACGUAUUGGUCACGUUGGAAUGCAAAUUGAGCACAUCAUUGAAAACAUUGUUGCUGUCACCAAAGGACUUUCAGAAAAAUUGCCAGAGAAGUGGGAGAGCGUGAAACUCCUGUUUGUGAAAACUGAGAAAUCGGCUGCACUUCCCAUCUUUUCCUCGUUUGUCAGCAAUUGGGAUGAAGCCACCAAAAGAUCUUUGCUUAAUAAGAAGAAAAAAGAGGCAAGGAGAAAACGAAGAGAAAGAAAUUUUGAAAAACAAAAGGAGAGGAAGAAGAAGAGGCAGCAGGCUAGGAAGACUGCAUCAGUUCUUAGUAAAGAUGAUGUGGCACCUGAAAGUGGUGAUACUACAGUGAAGAAACCUGAAUCAAAGAAGGAACAGACCCCAGAGCAUGGGAAGAAAAAACGUGGCAGAGGAAAAGCCCAAGUUAAAGCAACAAAUGAAUCCGAAGACGAAAUCCCACAGCUGGUACCAAUAGGAAAGAAGACUCCAGCUAAUGAAAAAGUAGAGAUUCAAAAACAUGCCACAGGAAAGAAGUCUCCAGCAAAGAGUCCUAAUCCCAGCACACCUCGUGGGAAGAAAAGAAAGGCUUUGCCAGCAUCUGAGACCCCAAAAGCUGCAGAGUCUGAGACCCCAGGGAAAAGCCCAGAGAAGAAGCCAAAAAUCAAAGAAGAGGCAGUGAAGGAAAAAAGUCCUUCGCUGGGGAAAAAAGAUGCGAGACAGACUCCAAAAAAGCCAGAGGCCAAGUUUUUCACCACUCCUAGUAAAUCUGUGAGAAAAGCUUCCCACACCCCCAAAAAAUGGCCCAAAAAACCCAAAGUACCCCAGUCGACCUAAAGUCAGUGAUUCAACUGGAAGGAAACCUCAAUGCUGCCUCCAGAGCUUUUUGGAAAUACUCAGAUCCUGGCCGCCUUUGUAACCUUCUCUAAACGUCAGGCCUGGACUUAAAAGAUUUUUUAAAACCUCCAUAAGUAGUCCAGGGGCGGUGGCUCACGCCUGUAAUCCCAGCACUUUGGGAGGCCGAGGCAGGCGGAUCACAAGGUCAACGAGAUCGAGACCAUCCUGGCCAACAUGGUGAAACCCUGUCUGUACCAAAAAUACAAAAAUUAAUUGGGCAUGGUGGUGGACACCUGUAAUCCCAGCUACUAGGGAGGCUGAGGCAGGAGAAUUGCUUGAACCUGGGAGGCGGAGGUUGCAGUGAGCCACUGCACUCCAGCCUGAUGACAGAGCAAGACUCAGUCUCAAAAAUAAAUAAAAAUAAUAAAACCUCCAUAAGUAAUCCUGACAUAUGUUCCUGGGUAUAAUCUGUUUCUAAAUUGUCCUUCUGUGUAUUUGCUAAUGUAAUAGAGGGAAAAAUAGAGUGCUUCUCUGUGGUUGUUCAGCACUUUAGGUAGCCAAGGUGAGAGGAUUGCUUGAGGCCAGGAGUUUGAGACUAGCCUGGGCAACUUGGUAAAACCCCAUCUCUACAAAAGAAAAAAAAAAAUUAGUGUGGCAUGGUGGCAUGCAUCUGUGCUCCCAGCUCCUCACGAGGCUGAGGUGGAAGGAUCAAGUGAGCGCAAGAGGUUGAGGCUCCAGUGAGCCACGAUCACCCCACUGUGCUGUAGCCUGGGUGACAGUGUGAGAUUCUGUCUCAGAAAAAACAAAGUAUAACAUUGCUUUGCUUCUGAGUAUACUGUUGGCUUUCCAAAUCAGUGGGUCUGACUUGAGGUCUGUGAUGUGACCCUUUUCCUCACCUGCUCAACCAUUAUUCACAUGGACUCCAUCAUAUUCAUUUGUAGUCAUUCCCAGAGUGGCCCAGUGAGGGUCUCGCUGUAUGAGAGUCGGCUACGGAAUUUAGGAGAAACAGAAGUUUCUUGGCUUUCAUGCUGAGCUUGUUGGUCUAAGCUUAUGAGUCACUGGAUUAGCAUCCAUAUGGGAAGGGAAAUUAACAUGGAGUCAUUUAUACAGGGACUAAAUUGAAUCCUACCUACCGGAGGCAAGAACAUGAUUUAUCUUCCAUAAGCCUUAUCCUCUUCCUCCUUAUUCCUCAGUCCAUAUGGAUUUGCUUAUGUAUGACAACUCCAAGGAAUCUUGGAAGAGUAGAUUGCUAACGUUUCCACAAUUGUCAAGUAUAUUCUGAGGCAGUAAACACCUUUUUAGGUACGUGGCCUUUCACUGGUUGUGAAUUGGUAUGCAUCCGUAGUAGUAAGUUCACAGAUUCACUGCAGUGCAGGAAUGUUCUUGCAUGCCAAAGACUCAACUGCUUUCAAAGAUAAUGUGGGUGCUAGAUGCAGUGGCUUACAUCUGUAACCCUGUUAGGGUGACCAGACCCAACACCAGGUCGUGGGGGUGACAAAGUCCAGUGGAGUCAAAGGAUUGAGAAAAAGACAGUUUGAGAGAGAAGUAGGACCAGCAGACCAUCGGGAUGGUGGAGGCUGUGAAGGCCGUGAGCUCUGGGAGCCCACACUAUUUAUUGGUAAUCCAACAAAGAAACAGAUGGUGAGAAUGUGAAGGUCAGAAGGGCACCUUGCAUUAAGCACAUGAUUUACAGCUGUGAUGGUUUAGCAUUUGCUCUGCUACUUGAGAUGAUGGAGAGCAGGUUCUUUUAACUCAAGUUACAGUCGAUCCUGGGAGAGCAAGGAGCCAGCAAGUCUAGACAUUCCAGAGCCACAGGCCCUGGAUUUUAUCCAAGCCACGAGGGAUUUUAUGCCCUGGGCUUAGAUUAUGGUGCGUCAGGGCAGCCUUCCACCCUUUAGCACAGAGCUUGGUGUUCCAAAGACCACAAGGGGUUUUAGACCCUUGACCCUGGACAUAUUCCAAGACUCUUUUACAUUAUGUCAGAAUGCAAGCCCUGCCUCAGCUUCUCCCAACACUCAGCUUUUCGCAACAUAAUCCCAGCACUUUGGAACGCUGGGUGGAUUGCUUGAACCCAGGAGUUCGAGACCAUCCUGGGCAAUAUGGCAAAACCCCAUCUUUACCAAAAAUAAGCUGGGUGUGGUGGAACAUGCCUGUGGUCCCAGCUUCUUGGGAGGCUGAGGUGGGAGGAUUGCUUGAACCCGGGAGGUAGAGGCUGCAAUGGGCCAUGAUCACGAUCCUGCACUCCAGCCUGGGCAACAGAGAGAGACAGUCCCUGGCCCACUGCCCCCUUCCCUGGCCCAGUCUCAAAAAAAAUGAGGCUGGGCGUGGUGGCUCACAUCUGUAAUCCCAGCCAAGGCUGGCAGAUCACUUGAGGCCAGGAGUUCUGAGACCAGCCUGGCUUACAUGGUGAAACCCCAUCUCUACUAAAAAUACAAAAACUAGCCAGGCAUGGUGGGAGGCACCUGUAAUCCCAGCUACUUGGGAGGCUGAAGCAGGAGAAUCACUUUAACCCGGGAGGUGGAGGUUGCAGUGAGCUGAGAUCACACCACUGCACUCCAGCCUGGGCGGCAGAGCAAAACUGAAAAAAAGAGAAAAAAAAAAACAUCUAGCUCUCCCUGAAAUUAGAGGAGUCUAGCCUGCUUUUGCUGUUUUUUUGGUAGCGAGAGUAGCGGGCAGUGGGGGAGAUGGUCUUACUCUGUUCCCCAGGCUGGAGUGCACUAGUGUCAUCACAGCUCCAGCCUCAAUUUCCUGGGCUCAAGGCGAUCUUCCCACCUCAGCCUCCCAAGUAGCUCAGACUACAGGGGCAUGCCAUCACAGCUGGCCAGUUUUUACGUCUUGCGUAGAGAUGGGUUUUCCCUGUGUUCCCUAGGCUGGGCUCGAACUCCUGGGCUCAAGUCCUCCUGCCUCAGCCUCCCAAAAUGUUCAGAUUACAGGCAUGAGGCAGCAUGCCAAUCCUGUUUUUGCAUUUUAGUAACACAAAUUGUAAUGUUAACUUUUUAAAUUAUGAAAGCAUCUAAAAUAUAAAAUUAUUUGUAACCCCACUGUCCUUUUGGGCUUCUAUAAAUGAAUAUACAUCUAAAAUGUGGGGGUUUAGCUUAAUUGAUUGUUUUCCAUAGAAACUAGGUUUUAUGGGAAGAUGGUUGGAUAGACUUGUUUCACUUAAAGGUCUGGUUUGUGUAGGACAAACCCACAUAUGUAAUCGUGCCAGUCUGUUCUCUGCAUGACAUAAUUUUCCAGCAAUAGCUGUGUGGUUUUUGUAAUCCUAUCAUCUAGUCAGUUCAAGAUCUUGCAACACUGUGUGAUUCUUUGCUCCGUAGUUCAGUCUUGUUGAACAUGACACAGGUGUUUACUUUCCUGUUCUUGCAUCUAGUUUCAUUCUAAUAAUGUUCUCUGUUGAAAAAGCUGGCUUCAAUUUAUUGAGCAAGAUGCUGGUGUUAUCAUCUAACAUAAAACCUAUCUUAUAAUAAAGUGUUGACACAUGUAAUGAGUACUGUACUGAAAAAUGGUGGUAUGUAUAUGGUUUGUACUGAUUAUGUAUCGCUUUUAUACCAUCAAAAAGUUGAAAAAUCAUAAAGUUGAAUCAUCCUAAAAUGGGUACAUUCUGUACUAUGUUUCCAAGGCUUCAGAAGUGUUGCAUACACAUUCCUAGCCAGCUGAUAGUGCUAGGAGCCAACAGUAGUCUCCCCCGGGGGCCAAGAGGAGGGCGAAAUCUCUACUAUGGUAUAUGAUGUUCUCGUGGGCCAAGUAUGAGGGUGAUAUUUCAUUGUUGGCACUGGGUUUCUGGAAUCCAUCCUCUUCACCAGGGAGAUUUAAUGAACCAAAUGAGAUCUGAUGGGAGAAAUUUGAGUGUAACGUUUUUGUUCUGAAGGAAGUAAUUGAGUUUUAGUUCAUUUGUUUUUUAGGAAUCGUAAUAAUUAAAAUUUCAUUUUAAAUGCCA